AGCUAGGAACUGCUGGCUAGGGCAAGCAGACAGCUGAAUCCUAGCCAACUGGAGGUGGAGCAGAGGUGGAGCCAGGGAGACCCAGGUGGCCUCUCUCAGAGUGGAGCACAGGUGGCAGAGUGGCCCGGGGCAGCAUGAAGUGGUGCUGGGGCCCAGUGCUGCUCAUCGCGGGUGCCACAGUCCUCAUGGAGGGUCUUCAAGCCGCUCAGCGUGCCUGUGGACAGCGUGGCCCCGGCCCCCCCAAGCCUCAGGAGGGCAACACAGUCCCUGGCGAGUGGCCCUGGCAGGCCAGUGUGAGGAGGCAAGGAGCCCACAUCUGCAGCGGCUCCCUGGUGGCAGACACCUGGGUCCUCACUGCUGCCCACUGCUUUGAAAAGGCAGCAGCAACAGAACUGAAUUCCUGGUCAGUGGUCCUGGGUUCUCUGCAGCGUGAGGGACUCAGCCCUGGGGCCGAAGAGGUGGGGGUGGCUGCCCUGCAGUUGCCCAGGGCCUAUAACCACUACAGCCAGGGCUCAGACCUGGCCCUGCUGCAGCUCGCCCACCCCACGACCCACACACCCCUCUGCCUGCCCCAGCCCGCCCAUCGCUUCCCCUUUGGAGCCUCCUGCUGGGCCACUGGCUGGGAUCAGGACACCAGUGAUGGUAAGUGCUGGCCCAGACUGAAGCUCGGAGAGGCACUCUGCUUGCCCAGCGUCACAGUCUCAGCUCCCAACUGUCCUGGCUUCCAGUCUCCCUUGCUUCCCAGAUCCCAGACUCUAGCCCCAGCCCCGUCUCUUUCACCAGCUCCUGGGACCCUACGCAAUCUGCGCCUGCGUCUCAUCAGUCGCCCCACAUGUAACUGUAUCUACAACCAGCUGCACCAGCGACACCUGUCCAACCCGGCCCGGCCUGGGAUGCUAUGUGGGGGCCCCCAGCCUGGGGUGCAGGGCCCCUGUCAGGGAGAUUCCGGGGGCCCUGUGCUGUGCCUCGAGCCUGACGGACACUGGGUUCAGGCUGGCAUCAUCAGCUUUGCAUCAAGCUGUGCCCAGGAGGACGCUCCUGUGCUGCUGACCAACACAGCUGCUCACAGUUCCUGGCUGCAGGCUCGAGUUCAGGGGGCAGCUUUCCUGGCCCAGAGCCCAGAGACCCCGGAGAUGAGUGAUGAGGACAGCUGUGUAGCCUGUGGAUCCUUGAGGACAGCAGGUCCCCAGGCAGGAGCACCCUCCCCAUGGCCCUGGGAGGCCAGGCUGAUGCACCAGGGACAGCUGGCCUGUGGCGGAGCCCUGGUGUCAGAGGAGGCGGUGCUAACUGCUGCCCACUGCUUCAUUGGGCGCCAGGCCCCAGAGGAAUGGAGCGUAGGGCUGGGGACCAGACCGGAGGAGUGGGGCCUGAAGCAGCUCAUCCUGCAUGGAGCCUACACCCACCCUGAGGGGGGCUACGACAUGGCCCUCCUGCUGCUGGCCCAGCCUGUGACACUGGGAGCCAGCCUGCGGCCCCUCUGCCUGCCCUAUCCUGACCACCACCUGCCUGAUGGGGAGCGUGGCUGGGUUCUGGGACGGGCCCGCCCAGGAGCAGGCAUCAGCUCCCUCCAGACAGUGCCCGUGACCCUCCUGGGGCCUAGGGCCUGCAGCCGGCUGCAUGCAGCUCCUGGGGGUGAUGGCAGCCCUAUUCUGCCGGGGAUGGUGUGUACCAGUGCUGUGGGUGAGCUGCCCAGCUGUGAGGGCCUGUCUGGGGCACCACUGGUGCAUGAGGUGAGGGGCACAUGGUUCCUGGCCGGGCUGCACAGCUUCGGAGAUGCUUGCCAAGGCCCCGCCAGGCCGGCGGUCUUCACCGCGCUCCCUGCCUAUGAGGACUGGGUCAGCAGUUUGGACUGGCAGGUCUACUUCGCCGAGGAACCAGAGCCCGAGGCUGAGCCUGGAAGCUGCCUGGCCAACAUAAGUAUGUGGCCCCGGGGCCUCCUGCCAAACCCUGCCUCUCCAGGACCCUUCUCUCUCCAGUGAGAACGUGCCGUUCUAACCCACUCCAGCUGCCUUGGGUAGGGUGGAGCAACAGGCAGACCCAUUUGAUUCAGAUUCUGGUUCUUUGUCAUCGUGUGACUUGGAGCAGGCUGCUCAACCGCUUUGAGCCUCAGUAUUCUCAUCUGUCAUGGCGGCCAAGACAGACCCUGUUCCUUCGAGGAAUGGGGAGGGAGGGAGGGACCAAAGCCGUGAGGAUGAGGACAACUCCACCCUCCUUCCUUCCCCACAGGCCAACCAACCAGCUGCUGACAGGGGACCUGGCCAUUCUCAGGACAAGAGAAUGCAGGCAGGCAAAUGGCAUUACUGCCCCUGUCCUCCCCACCCUGUCAUGUGUGAUUCCAGGCACCAGGGCAGGCCCAGAAGCCCAGCAGCUGUGGGAAGGAACCUGCCUGGGGCCACAGGUGCCCACUCCCCACCCUGCAGGACAGGGGUGUCUGUGGACACUCCCACACCCAACUCUGCUACCAAGCAGGCGUCUCAGCUUUCCUCCUCCUUUACCCUUUCAGAUACAAUCACGCCAGCCACGUUGUUUUGAAAAUUUCUUUUUUUGGGGGGCAGCAGUUUUCCUUUUUUUAAACUUAAAUAAAUUGUUACAAAAUAGA